AUGAGACCCGCUCGAGCGGAGGACCAGCAGCCAGCCCGACGCUGAUGGUUCUUACCUCGUACUAAAACCUUUGCUUUGACACAGUUUUAGAGUUGCUUAAUAUUCGAGCAAGCACCUGACACGGGUGACUUUCUCCUUCUUUUUUUCCUCCGGUCCCUCGGGUAAGAUGGAGGUAGAAAAUGAAGCCAGCUGCUCCCCGGGCAGCGCAUCAGGCGGGUCCAGAGAGUACAAGGUGGUAAUGCUGGGAGCAGGGGGAGUUGGUAAAAGCGCAAUGACAAUGCAGUUUAUUAGUCAUCAGUUCCCUGAUUAUCAUGACCCUACUAUAGAAGAUGCUUAUAAGACCCAGGUCAGGAUUGACAAUGAGCCAGCUUACUUGGACAUCUUGGACACUGCUGGCCAGGCAGAAUUCACAGCCAUGCGGGAGCAGUACAUGCGAGGUGGGGAAGGCUUCAUCAUCUGCUACUCCGUCACUGACCGUCAAUCAUUUCAGGAGGCUGCCAAGUUUAAAGAGCUCAUUUUUCAGGUCCGCCACACCUAUGAAAUUCCCCUGGUGCUGGUGGGUAACAAAAUUGAUCUGGAACAGUUCCGCCAGCCUACACUGAAAGAGUUUGGAAGGGAAGAAUUCUGAUGGUUGAAGCUGCUUCUUUUCAUAUUUGGUUUCUACAGAAGAAGGCUUGAGUCUUGCCCAAGAAUAUAAUUGUGGUUUUUUUGAGACCUCUGCAGCCCUCAGAUUCUGUAUUGAUGAUGCUUUUCAUGGCUUAGUGAGGGAAAUUCGCAAGAAGGAGUCCAUGCCAUCCUUGAUGGAAAAGAAACUGAAGAGAAAAGACAGCCUGUGGAAGAAGCUCAAAGGUUCUUUGAAGAAGAAGAGAGAAAAUAUGACAUGAUAUCUUUGCUUUUGAGUUCCUCACGCUCUCUGAAUUUUAUUAGUUGGACAAUUCCAUAUGUAGCAUUCUGCUUCAAUAUUAUCUCUCUAUGUGUCUCUCUCUCUUUAAAUAUCUGCCUGUAGGUAAAAGCAAGCUCUGCAUAUCUGUACCUCUUGAGAUAGUUUUGUUUUGCCUUUAACAGUUGGAUGGAUUUUGUCAAUCAGCUGGAUAUGCUGUUUAGUUUUUACAACAUAGUACUAAAUAAAAUUGACAUUCCAAUUGCCUCA